GGAAAGGCUACGUAUUCAGCCCUGGAGGUGCCAUCCCGGGCCGCGACUCCGCUCCAGGCAGGACCCCCAACCCGCCCAGCCCGCUCCGCCUUGCGCCCCGGACCCGCGGCCGACCCCAGACCCGCUGCCCGCUUCGCGCCCGAGGCCUGCGCCCCGACGGACGCCCGUGCCCAGCUUGCCACGCCCACGCCCGGCGCCCCGACCGCGGAGGACUCCCCGAGGUGCCGGCGGAGGGGGUGGCUCGCGGCUCAGGCUGCCCCCGACGUGCCCGGCUCACCGCCCCCUCCCCUGCAGCCCCGCCCGCCAUGGCCCGGAUCCCGACGGCCGCCCUGGGUUGCAUCAGCCUCCUCUGCCUGCAGCUCCCUGGCUCGCUGUCCCGCAGCCUGGGCGGGGACCCGCGACCCGUCAAACCCAGGGAGCCCCCAGCCCGGAGCCCUUCCAGCAGCCUGCAGCCCAGGCACCCCGCACCCCGACCUGUGGUCUGGAAGCUUCACCGGGCCCUCCAGGCACAGAGGGGUGCCGGCCUGGCCCCUGUUAUGGGUCAGCCUCUCCGGGAUGGUGGCCGCCAACACUCGGGCCCCCGAAGACACUCGGGCCCCCGCAGGACCCAAGCCCAGCUCCUGCGAGUGGGCUGUGUGCUGGGCACCUGCCAGGUGCAGAAUCUCAGCCACCGCCUGUGGCAACUCAUGGGACCGGCCGGCCGGCAGGACUCAGCUCCUGUGGACCCCAGCAGCCCCCACAGCUAUGGCUGAGGUGGGGCCGGGCCACACCCCUGCCCAUCCCAGCCAGGGUGCUGUGCCCCCGUCCAGAGCUGCAGCUGAGCCCCAUCUGAAGCCCAGUCCCUCGGAGCUGCAGACAGCAGGUCCUGCAGCAACAAUACCUGCACGGCUUUGCACACGUAAACCUAGGCUGGUCUACACGCAGUGCUGGUACGUCAAGGAGCCUAAACACCCUGAAAUUGUGACCCCCUGGGGGACAGCUGCCAGACACAGCUGGCGGCAGCACCAGAUGCUAAGCGCUUCAGAGAGGAGGUGUCUGCCCAGAGAUGUGGAGCAGAAGCUGGGCCCUGAACACACGGGGCCAUGUCUGGACGAGCAGGGGAGAGAGGCUGAACUGGCCAGAAGUGGCCCCUCCGCUGCUGGUCCAGUCAGACUGAAGCCCGGCCUUGUGCCUGGGCUGUUCCUGCUCUCAUGCACAACCAGCCCUUCCACGUGCCUGCCUGUGGGACAGGAGGGGGAGCGUGGGAUGCUGUAGCCCCCGGGGUUGGGCAAGGGAAGGAUGGUGGCCCUCCAGAGGUCAUGAAGGGACCUCUGUGGCUCCAGCUGCCAACCCUGGAGCCCAGACCGAGGUGGCCAUGGAGACUCCACCUGGAUCCCCUGUAGGAGGCCAGGGAGGGGAACUCAGCAGUUCAGGAGCCACCCCAAACCAUUCUGGGACAGGGACACCCCUUUCUACCCCAGGGCAGGGCAGGGCUGGGUGGGGCAAGAUCCCCCAGCCCGACUAGACCCACCUCACCUGAAGGGGGUGAGACCCUUGUUGGCAGCCAGACAAGGGUGGGGCUCCACAGGCAGCACAGGCGCCCCACCACCACCCAGUUUGGGGACCCAGUGGGACCAGGUGCGGGGGCAGAGGGUGACUUACCAAGAGCCAGGGAGGGCAGCCCAGGCCCAAGUGACAGCAAGAACAAGAACCACUGCCGGCGUGCACAGACUUGGUGUGUGUCCUUCCCUGGGGGGACGGGGGACUCACAUGUGCCUGCCACUGGAGCCUCUCAACCGUCCAGCAGAACACGGGGUUCAGAAAGGGCUCCUUCUGCUAUUUAGCGAACACUGAGCAUUUAAUUUACAAAUGUUUGCUAGGGUCACCCUCUCGGCCAUCCCACGAGGGUCGCCAUGAUCACCCCAACUCUAGAGGCCGCAGCAGAGCUCAGGACAUUCCCCCACAGAGCUUGCCCCUCAGUUCCUACCUCCAAGGGGGAGGGUCCUGGAAGCGCCCACCCAGGCGCCGCCCCUGUGCUUGCUCCCCGAGCUCAGGGAUUGCCGAGUCCACGUAACUGACCUGUACUCCACGAGGCCCUGUGGGAACGGUCCAGGCUGGUCCUGCCCUGUGGAGGCCUCCGUGCACUGAGAGAUGUACUAGGAUUGCAGCAAAGGUGGUCAGGGUGAUGGGCCGCACAGCGAGGCAGUCAAGGCCAGCUCCCUGGGAGAAGCACUGGGUCAGGUGAGGUCUGAGGACAGCAGGCCUUCCCUAGGGGAAGGAGCUGGGAGUGCCAAGGCCCCAGGUGCACAGGAGGCGUGGCUGCUGAGAGGCUGCAGGGUGGAGGGGCCUCGGCCUCAGAGUCAUGUGCCCUGUGACCACUGAAGGGUGUCAGCAGAGCACACGGCAUGAGGACAGAGGGAGGGGCACGGGGAGUGAAGGAGGGGGCCCUGGGGCAAGGCUCGGGGGUCAGGAGCUCAGCGUCCGCUACUCAGCCCAGCCAAAACCCUCCCAGACGUCUCCUCUCCUGCCUGGGCAAAGUCCAGCUUGGCACCCCGUCUGGGGCCUGCCUGUGGUCAGGGCCAAGUGUUCCCUCCUCCAGGAAAGCCUUUACCCUCCUCAUGCCCUGUAGUCAGGAGGCCGCCUGCUGUAACCCUCCGUGUCGCCUCGGGUGCGAAAUCAGACCCACCUGACACCAUCACGCGGAGGCCCAGCAGCACCUGCACCCACUUCCAGCUGCUCUGGCCAAAAUCUCCGCUCGGCCAGGCCCCGUGGCUCACACCUGUAAUCCUAGCACAUUGGGAGGCCAAGGCAGGCACAUCACCUGAGUUCAGGAGUUCAAGACCAGCCUGGCCAACAUGGUGAAAUCCCGUCUCUACUAAAAACAGAAAAUUAUCCGGGCGUGGUGGCACAUGACUGUAAUCCCAGCUACUCAGGAGGCUGAGGCAGGAGGAUCACUUGAACCUGGGAGGCGGAGGUUGCAGUGAGCUGAGAUUGCGCCAUUGCACUCCAGCCUGGGCAACAAGAGCAAAAUUCUGCCUCAAAAAAAAAAAUAGUAAUAAUACAAAAAUUAGCUGGGCGUGGUGGCACAUGCCAGUAAUUCCAUCUACUCGGGAGGCUGAGGCAGGAGAAUCGUCUAAGCCCGGGAGGUGGAGGUUGCAGUGAGCCCAGAUGGCGCUGCUGCACUCAAGCUUGGAUGACAGAGCAAGACUCCGUUUCAAAAAAAAAAAACCUCCUCUCUUCCUUCACACCUUCCUCUGAAUCCCACCCGGUCCCACCUCCUGAACCUAUCCAGACACCUUCUCCUGACCCAGGCACCACCUGCUUUCGGGGCGAUGGCCGUAGCCUCCUCCCAGGCACCUGUCUGCAUCCCUCUGGCCAGUGCAUGCUGAGCACGUGACCUACCCGUGUUGGGACACGUGAGGAUACAGCCUUGACCCCCAGGGGCUGACAUUCUAGGGGGAGAUAGAAGGAGACAAACGUAGAAGGUAGAAUAAGUGGGUGGUGGAGUGGCAGGGAGUGCUGAGUGCCACAGGAAGUCAGACAAGGAAGGAGAGUGUGGGGCAGGUGCCGUUUAAAUGGGGGGCGCUGGGGUCUCCUCACAGUUGCUUCUCAGCUCAGCUGUGCCAGGAUCUUGUUGAGUCAGGUCAGCUGCCCACAGCCCUCUUGCCUGACCCCUGAAGCCCAGAACUCUGAUCUUCACAGCCCUAGGUAUGGCCCCAGCACCCCACUGCCCUCUCUCCUGCCCCAGCCGACUGCUGUUCCCAGACUUCCCUGGCCACGCUCCAAGACGCCAGCUCUGCCGCGGGCACUUUGUUCUCACGGUGUCCUCCAUGCCUGCAGGGCCCAUGCAUGGGAAGUUGCGUUGGCGGCCUGGGUGUUGGCGGUUCCGUGCCUGCUCCAACUCUCCGUGAGGCCCCUCUCCCAGAGCCUGACACACUCUGUGGCCGAACUCUAGGCAGGUGCCCCUGAGUCCUUUCCUCGACGAGGCCUGACCCCAUCCCCAUCCUCGCUGGGCCCGCCGACCCCGGUGUUAGCAAGAAUCCUCUAAAUCAGUUUAUGGAGAAUUACCCACCCUCGAUAUCUGAUCCCAUUCCUCAUCUCCCACCCUUGAUCUCAUCACCCUGCCGGCCUCCUGCAAGAUCCUCAUUGAGCCACUCCAGUGAGAAUCCCCCUACCCUCGAAGGCCGCCCUAACAACUUCCCAUCCGCUGACCCCUCCAACGCCAUCAAUCUCCAGCUGUGGUUGUUGAACUCGGAGGUGAGCUCCUCUCACCACUCUCUUGAAUAAAGCUUUUCUCACCAUUUUAA